GGAAGUUUUCGCUGGGCAACUGAGAAGGUGAGUCCGGGUAACUGCGGAGGAUCCGAGGGUCAGGCUGCAGAAGCCCAGAAUCCCACCCCAGUCCCCAAGUACAGAGGUGAGGGGAAGCGAGGCGAACGAGGGGACGUCCCCCGACCCCCUAGCCGCAGCUCGGCCGGGGCGUCCGUGACGUCAGCACGACCGUUUGUGGGAGGCGGAGGCCCCUGCUGUCGGGGUUCGGAAUGAGAGCGGCUCCGGGUCGCGGGGUUCACUGGCCUCCUCUUGAGCUUCCCAAGCCACCUUGGGCUCCGUGUUGGGCAUGGCUAAGGCGGAGAUGGGCGGAACUUGUGGGAAGUUCGACAGCUCCUCCGCUGUGAAACUUGGCGUCUAAGUCAUCCCGUGGUUUCUAUGGAGGUGCGGCCGAAGGGAGGCUCUGUCGUCGCCUAGGCAAUCGCCCCACCUGCGCUGAGGUCGCUGUCAAGAUGGAGUUUCCAACCCAGUAAAUCCAAGGGCCAGACCGUGACCUCAUAAAGCAUGAUCUCCUUCUGUCCAGACUGUGGCAAAAGUAUCCAAGCGGCAUUCAAAUUCUGCCCCUACUGUGGAAAUUCUUUGCCUGUAGAGGAGCAUGUAGGGUCCCAGACCUUUGUCAAUCCACAUGUGUCAUCCUUCCAAGGCUCAAAGAGAGGGCUGAACUCCAGUUUUGAAACCUCUCCUAAGAAAGUGAAAUGGUCCAGCACCGUCACCUCUCCCCGAUUAUCCCUCUUCUCAGAUGGUGACAGUUCUGAGUCUGAAGAUACUCUGAGUUCCUCUGAGAGAUCCAAAGGCUCCGGGAGCAGACCCCCAACCCCCAAAAGCAGCCCUCAGAAGACCAGGAAGAGCCCUCAGGUGACCAGGGGUAGCCCUCAGAAGACCAGCUGUAGCCCUCAGAAGACCAGGCAGAGCCCUCAGACGCUGAAGCGGAGCCGAGUGACCACCUCACUUGAAGCUUUGCCCACAGGGACAGUGCUGACAGACAAGAGUGGGCGACAGUGGAAGCUGAAGUCCUUCCAGACCAGGGACAACCAGGGCAUUCUCUAUGAAGCUGCACCCACCUCCACCCUCACCUGUGACUCAGGACCACAGAAGCAAAAGUUCUCACUCAAACUGGAUGCCAAGGAUGGGCGCUUGUUCAAUGAGCAGAACUUCUUCCAGCGGGCCGCCAAGCCUCUGCAAGUCAACAAGUGGAAGAAGCUGUACUCGACCCCACUGCUGGCCAUCCCUACCUGCAUGGGUUUCGGUGUUCACCAGGACAAAUACAGGUUCUUGGUGUUACCCAGCCUGGGGAGGAGCCUUCAGUCGGCCCUGGAUGUCAGCCCAAAGCAUGUGCUGUCAGAGAGGUCUGUGCUGCAGGUGGCCUGCCGGCUGCUGGAUGCCCUGGAGUUCCUCCAUGAGAAUGAGUAUGUUCAUGGAAAUGUGACAGCUGAAAAUAUCUUUGUGGAUCCAGAGGACCAGAGUCAGGUGACUUUGGCAGGCUAUGGCUUCGCCUUCCGCUAUUGCCCAAGUGGCAAACACGUGGCCUACGUGGAAGGCAGCAGGAGCCCUCACGAGGGGGACCUUGAGUUCAUUAGCAUGGACCUGCACAAGGGAUGCGGGCCCUCCCGCCGCAGCGACCUCCAGAGCCUGGGCUACUGCAUGCUGAAGUGGCUCUACGGGUUUCUGCCAUGGACAAAUUGCCUUCCCAACACUGAGGACAUCAUGAAGCAAAAACAGAAGUUUGUUGAUAAGCCGGGGCCCUUCGUGGGACCCUGCGGUCACUGGAUCAGGCCCUCAGAGACCCUGCAGAAGUACCUGAAGGUGGUGAUGGCCCUCACGUAUGAGGAGAAGCCGCCCUACGCCAUGCUGAGGAACAACCUAGAAGCUUUGCUGCAGGAUCUGCGUGUGUCUCCAUAUGACCCCAUUGGCCUCCCGAUGGUGCCCUAGGUGGAAUCCAGAACUUUCCAUUUGCAGUGUGCAACAGAAAAAAAAAAAUGAAGUAAUGUGACUCAAGGCCUGCUGUUUAAUCACAGAUAAGCUUCUAGAACAAGCCCUGGAAUGUGCAUUCCUGCCACUGGUUUCAGGAUACUCAUCAGUCCUGAUUAGCCUCCCGGAGGGCCCCAGUUUCCCUCCCGUGAAUGUGAAGUUCCCCAUCUUGGUGGCCUGCCCUUCAGCCAGUGUCCUAGCAAAGCUGGAUGGGGUUGGGCCGGCCCACAGGGGGGACCCCUCCUACCCUUGACACCUCUGUGCUUUGGUAAUAAAUUGUUUUACCAGA